GAUGUUAUCUGCUGGCAGCAGAAGGUUCGCUCCGAGCGGAGCUCCAGAAGCUCCUGACAAGAGAAAGACAGAUUGAGAUAGAGAUAGAAAGAGAAAGAGAGAAAGAGACAGCAGAGCGAGAGCGCAAGUGAAAGAGGCAGGGGAGGGGGAUGGAGAAUAUUAGCCUGACGGUCUAGGGAGUCAUCCAGGAACAAACUGAGGGGCUGCCCGGCUGCAGACAGGAGGAGACAGAGAGGAUCUAUUUUAGGGUGGCAAGUGCCUACCUACCCUAAGCGAGCAAUUCCACGUUGGGGAGAAGCCAGCAGAGGUUGGGAAAGGGUGGGAGUCCAAGGGAGCCCCUGCGCAACCCCCUCAGGAAUAAAACUCCCCAGCCAGGGUGUCGCAAGGGCUGCCGUUGUGAUCCGCAGGGGGUGAACGCAACCGCGACGGCUGAUCGUCUGUGGCUGGGUUGGCGUUUGGAGCAAGAGAAGGAGGAGCAGGAGAAGGAGGGAGCUGGAGGCUGGAAGCGUUUGCAAGCGGCGGCGGCAGCAACGUGGAGUAACCAAGCGGGUCAGCGCGCGCCCGCCAGGGUGUAGGCCACGGAGCGCAGCUCCCAGAGCAGGAUCCGCGCCGCCUCAGCAGCCUCUGCGGCCCCUGCGGCACCCGACCGAGUACCGAGCGCCCUGCGAAGCGCACCCUCCUCCCCGCGGUGCGCUGGGCUCGCCCCCAGCGCGCGCACACGCACACACACACACACACACACACACGCACGCACACACGUGUGCGCUUCUCUGCUCCGGAGCUGCUGCUGCUCCUGCUCUCAGCGCCGCAGUGGAAGGCAGGACCGAACCGCUCCUUCUUUAAAUAUAUAAAUUUCAGCCCAGGUCAGCCUCGGCGGCCCCCCUCACCGCGCUCCCGGCGCCCCUCCCGUCAGUUCGCCAGCUGCCAGCCCCGGGACCUUUUCAUCUCUUCCCUUUUGGCCGGAGGAGCCGAGUUCAGAUCCGCCACUCCGCACCCGAGACUGACACACUGAACUCCACUUCCUCCUCUUAAAUUUAUUUCUACUUAAUAGCCACUCGUCUCUUUUUUUCCCCAUCUCAUUGCUCCAAGAAUUUUUUUCUUCUUACUCGCCAAAGUCAGGGUUCCCUCUGCCCGUCCCGUAUUAAUAUUUCCACUUUUGGAACUACUGGCCUUUUCUUUUUAAAGGAAUUCAAGCAGGAUACGUUUUUCUGUUGGGCAUUGACUAGAUUGUUUGCAAAAGUUUCGCAUCAAAAACAACAACAACAAAAAACCAAACAACUCUCCUUGAUCUAUACUUUGAGAAUUGUUGAUUUCUUUUUUUUAUUCUGACUUUUAAAAACAACUUUUUUUUCCACUUUUUUAAAAAAUGCACUACUGUGUGCUGAGCGCUUUUCUGAUCCUGCAUCUGGUCACGGUCGCGCUCAGCCUGUCUACCUGCAGCACACUCGAUAUGGACCAGUUCAUGCGCAAGAGGAUCGAGGCGAUCCGCGGGCAGAUCCUGAGCAAGCUGAAGCUCACCAGUCCCCCAGAAGACUAUCCUGAGCCCGAGGAAGUCCCCCCGGAGGUGAUUUCCAUCUACAACAGCACCAGGGACUUGCUCCAGGAGAAGGCGAGCCGGAGGGCGGCCGCCUGCGAGCGCGAGAGGAGCGACGAAGAGUACUACGCCAAGGAGGUUUACAAAAUAGACAUGCCGCCCUUCUUCCCCUCCGAAACUGUCUGCCCAGUUGUUACAACACCCUCUGGCUCAGUGGGCAGCUUGUGCUCCAGACAGUCCCAGGUGCUCUGUGGGUACCUUGAUGCCAUCCCGCCCACUUUCUACAGACCCUACUUCAGAAUUGUUCGAUUUGACGUCUCAGCAAUGGAGAAGAAUGCUUCCAAUUUGGUGAAAGCAGAGUUCAGAGUCUUUCGUUUGCAGAACCCAAAAGCCAGAGUGCCUGAACAACGGAUUGAGCUAUAUCAGAUUCUCAAGUCCAAAGAUUUAACAUCUCCAACCCAGCGCUACAUCGACAGCAAAGUUGUGAAAACAAGAGCAGAAGGCGAAUGGCUCUCCUUCGAUGUAACUGAUGCUGUUCAUGAAUGGCUUCACCAUAAAGACAGGAACCUGGGAUUUAAAAUAAGCUUACACUGUCCCUGCUGCACUUUUGUACCAUCUAAUAAUUACAUCAUCCCAAAUAAAAGUGAAGAACUAGAAGCAAGAUUUGCAGGUAUUGAUGGCACCUCCACAUAUACCAGUGGUGAUCAGAAAACUAUAAAGUCCACUAGGAAAAAAAACAGUGGGAAGACCCCACAUCUCCUGCUAAUGUUAUUGCCCUCCUACAGACUUGAGUCACAACAGACCAACCGGCGGAAGAAGCGUGCUUUGGAUGCGGCCUAUUGCUUUAGAAAUGUGCAGGAUAAUUGCUGCCUACGUCCACUUUACAUUGAUUUCAAGAGGGAUCUAGGGUGGAAAUGGAUACACGAACCCAAAGGGUACAAUGCCAACUUCUGUGCUGGAGCAUGCCCGUAUUUAUGGAGUUCAGACACUCAGCACAGCAGGGUCCUGAGCUUAUAUAAUACCAUAAAUCCAGAAGCAUCUGCUUCUCCUUGCUGCGUGUCCCAAGAUUUAGAACCUCUAACCAUUCUCUACUACAUUGGCAAAACACCCAAGAUUGAACAGCUUUCUAAUAUGAUUGUAAAGUCUUGCAAAUGCAGCUAAAAUUCUUGGAAAAGUGGCAAGACCAAAAUGACAAUGAUGAUGAUAAUGAUGAUGACGACGACAACGAUGAUGCUUGUAACAAGAAAACAUAAGAGAGCCUUGGUUCAUCAGUGUUAAAAAAUUUUUGAAAAGGCGGUACUAGUUCAGACACUUUGGAAGUUUGUGUUCUGUUUGUUAAAACUGGCAUCUGACACAAAAAAAGUUGAAGGCCUUAUUCUACAUUUCACCUACUUUGUAAGUGAGAGAGACAAGAAGCAAAUUUUUUUUAAAGAAAAAAAUAAACACUGGAAGAAUUUAUUAGUGUUAAUUAUGUGAACAACGACAACAACAACAACAACAACAAACAGGAAAAUCCCAUUAAGUGGAGUUGCUGUACGUACCGUUCCUAUCCCGCGCCUCACUUGAUUUUUCUGUAUUGCUAUGCAAUAGGCACCCUUCCCAUUCUUACUCUUAGAGUUAACAGUGAGUUAUUUAUUGUGUGUUACUAUAUAAUGAACGUUUCAUUGCCCUUGGAAAAUAAAACAGGUGUAUAAAGUGGAGACCAAAUACUUUGCCAGAAACUCAUGGAUGGCUUAAGGAACUUGAACUCAAACGAGCCAGAAAAAAAGAGGUCAUAUUAAUGGGAUGAAAACCCAAGUGAGUUAUUAUAUGACCGAGAAAGUCUGCAUUAAGAUAAAGACCCUGAAAACACAUGUUAUGUAUCAGCUGCCUAAGGAAGCUUCUUGUAAGGUCCAAAAACUAAAAAGACUGUUAAUAAAAGAAACUUUCAGUCAGAAUAAGUCUGUAAGUUUUUUUUUUUCUUUUUAAUUGUAAAUGGUUCUUUGUCAGUUUAGUAAACCAGUGAAAUGUUGAAAUGUUUUGACAUGUACUGGUCAAACUUCAGACCUUAAAAUAUUGCUGUAUAGCUAUGCUAUAGGUUUUUUCCUUUGUUUUGGUAUAUGUAACCAUACCUAUAUUAUUAAAAUAGAUGGAUAUAGAAGCCAGCAUAAUUGAAAACACAUCUGCAGAUCUCUUUUGCAAACUAUUAAAUCAAAACAUUAACUACUUUAUGUGUAAUGUGUAAAUUUUUACCAUAUUUUUUAUAUUCUGUAAUAAUGUCAACUAUGAUUUAGAUUGACUUAAAUUUGGGCUCUUUUUAAUGAUCACUCACAAAUGUAUGUUUCUUUUAGCUGGCCAGUACUUUUGAGUAAAGCCCCUAUAGUUUGACUUGCACUACAAAUGCAUUUUUUUUUUAAUAACAUUUGCCCUACUUGUGCUUUGUGUUUCUUUCAUUAUUAUGACAUAAGCUACCUGGGUCCACUUGUCUUUUCUUUUUUUUGUUUCACAGAAAAGAUGGGUUCGAGUUCAGUGGUCUUCAUCUUCCAAGCAUCAUUACUAACCAAGUCAGACGUUAACAAAUUUUUAUGUUAGGAAAAGGAGGAAUGUUAUAGAUACAUAGAAAAUUGAAGUAAAAUGUUUUCAUUUUAGCAAGGAUUUAGGGUUCUAACUAAAACUCAGAAUCUUUAUUGAGUUAAGAAAAGUUUCUCUACCUUGGUUUAAUCAAUAUUUUUGUAAAAUCCUAUUGUUAUUACAAAGAGGACACUUCAUAGGAAACAUCUUUUUCUUUAGUCAGGUUUUUAAUAUUCAGGGGGAAAUUGAAAGAUAUAUAUUUUAGUCGAUUUUUCAAAAGGGGAAAAAAGUCCAGGUCAGCAUAAGUCAUUUUGUGUAUUUCACUGAAGUUAUAAGGUUUUUAUAAAUGUUCUUUGAAGGGGAAAAGGCACAAGCCAAUUUUUCCUAUGAUCAAAAAAUUCUUUCUUUCCUCUGAGUGAGAGUUAUCUAUAUCUGAGGCUAAAGUUUACCUUGCUUUAAUAAAUAAUUUGCCACAUCAUUGCAGAAGAGGUAUCCUCAUGCUGGGGUUAAUAGAAUAUGUCAGUUUAUCACUUGUCGCUUAUUUAGCUUUAAAAUAAAAAUUAAUAGGCAAAGCAAUGGAAUAUUUGCAGUUUCACCUAAAGAGCAGCAUAAGGAGGCGGGAAUCCAAAGUGAAGUUGUUUGAUAUGGUCUACUUCUUUUUUGGAAUUUCCUGACCAUUAAUUAAAGAAUUGGAUUUGCAAGUUUGAAAACUGGAAAAGCAAGAGAUGGGAUGCCAUAAUAGUAAACAGCCCUUGUGUUGGAUGUAACCCAAUCCCAGAUUUGAGUGUGUGUUGAUUAUUUUUUUGUCUUCCACUUUUCUAUUAUGUGUAAAUCACUUUUAUUUCUGCAGACAUUUUCCUCUCAGAUAGGAUGACAUUUUGUUUUGUAUUAUUUUGUCUUUCCUCAUGAAUGCACUGAUAAUAUUUUAAAUGCUCUAUUUUAAGAUCUCUUGAAUCUGUUUUUUUUUUUUUUAAUUUGGGGGUUCUGUAAGGUCUUUAUUUCCCAUAAGUAAAUAUUGCCAUGGGAGGGGGGUGGAGGUGGCAAGGAAGGGGUGAAGUGCUAGUAUGCAAGUGGGCAGCAAUUAUUUUUGUGUUAAUCAGCAGUACAAUUUGAUCGUUGGCAUGGUUAAAAAAUGGAAUAUAAGAUUAGCUGUUUUGUAUUUUGAUGACCAAUUACGCUGUAUUUUAACACGAUGUAUGUCUGUUUUUGUGGUGCUCUAGUGGUAAAUAAAUUAUUUCGAUGAUAUGUGGAUGUCUUUUUCCUAUCAGUACCAUCAUCGAGUCUAGAAAACACCUGUGAUGCAAUAAGACUAUCUCAAGCUGGAAAAGUCAUACCACCUUUCCGAUUGCCCUCUGUGCUUUCUCCCUUAAGGACAGUCACUUCAGAAGUCAUGCUUUAAAGCACAAGAGUCAGGCCAUAUCCAUCAAGGAUAGAAGAAAUCCCUGUGCCGUCUUUUUAUUCCCUUAUUUAUUGCUAUUUGGUAAUUGUUUGAGAUUUAGUUUCCAUCCAGCUUGACUGCCGACCAGAAAAAAUGCAGAGAGAUGUUUGCACCAUGCUUUGGCUUUCUGGUUCUAUGUUCUGCCAACGCCAGGGCCAAAAGAACUGGUCUAGACAGUAUCCCCUGUAGCCCCAUAACUUGGAUAGUUGCUGAGCCAGCCAGAUAUAACAAGAGCCACGUGCUUUCUGGGGUUGGUUGUUUGGGAUCAGCUACUUGCCUGUCAGUUUCACUGGUACCACUGCACCACAAACAAAAAAACCCACCCUAUUUCCUCCAAUUUUUUUGGCUGCUACCUACAAGACCAGACUCCUCAAACGAGUUGCCAAUCUCUUAAUAAAUAGGAUUAAUAAAAAAAGUAAUUGUGACUCAA